ACAUUUCAGCAAGCUGGCUAAAGACAUGUGGGAAAGCCUGACCCUGGAUUCAGGUCAAAUCUCAGCACUCACAAGAGUAAGUUCAUGCCUCUGUGUAUACAGUUAGAGCUGAAUAUGCUUUUGUUCUGAAGCUUUUAUUUUUAAAAAAUUAGACUUGACCUGUACUACAUAUGUGUAGGUUUCACCCUGUCUAUACCUGUCUGGGCAGGUUGUUUGGUUUGUUUUAAACUAAUAUUUAUUCAUAGCCAGGCACUGAGUUAGUGUCACAUAAAUGAGGCCCUUGGCAGUGAGGUCUGGCAGGCCCAUCAGCUUGGAGGGAAGGGUUCUGUGAUGUGCCCAUUGCCAGGAAUACUUUCCUUCCUCUACCUUCAUGGAAGGGGAUAAAACUCUUUAGUUCUCAGCUAAAACAUCUUCCAGGAGGCUGCCUCUGCCUCAUAGACUGAACCACAGGCCCAACGUGCAUCCUACUUUAAUGGUGAUUACUUGUUUGAUUAACUGUAUUCCUUUAAUGGUGAUUACUUGUUUGAUAACUGUAUUACCUGCCAUAAUGUAAGCAGGGCAGUGACUGUGCCCCCAUGGCCACUUAUGGGGUGAGUAUCUAGCUGUGCAGGGUAGGUGCUAAAAUGUUUGUUAGCUGGCUGAGUAAAUGCACUUUAAAAAAUUGUGUGUAGGAGGAGAGGGCCCUAUAAAGGCACAAAUUGGAAGGGAAAUUGCAGUGAAAGGGAUAUUGGGAGGAGAGUGGCAAUUUAGAUCGGAAAUCAAAGAGGAUGAGGAGACUGGGGACACAAUUUAUAGAAACGGCUGUAGAGUUCCCCAGAGAGAGCUCAUUCAUUCAUUCAUUCAUUCAUUCAACAAAUACCUCCUCUUCUGGUCCCCACUGUGUGCUGGGUGCACUGUGCAGGCCUUUUGUGAGUGUGUAUGUGAGUGUGUGUGUGAGUGUGUAUGUGAGUGUGUGAGUGUGUGAGUGUGUGUGUGAGUGUGUAUGUGAGUGUGUAUGUGUGUGUAGUUCUUUUCCACUUUAUCACAGGUAGAACCUUUAAAUUUUUUUUUCCUCCUAAGUUCGUCACUGUAUUAUUAACGUCUCUUCAAAAAUAGACUACACCAGUUCUUUACCCCUUGCUGGGAAAACUGAGAAGGCCGUUGAAAUGUUGGUCUUUGUUUUUUGCCCUGUUGUCCCCUGUUGCUAAGCAUUGGGGCACCUUGUGUUUUUUGGGCACUCUGUAUGGAGUCUGUACUUCUCUGCGGGUGUUUUUUUUUUGUUUUUUGUUUUUUUUGCAAGAUGCAUGGGUGGUAGGUAGUGGGUCACCAAGAUAGUCCCUUUUAGGGGCAAUGAUGUGGGGUAUAUUCUUGGCUAUUACCCUGUUGAGAUGAGUUUGGUCUUUUGGUCAAUUUCAUUGUAACUUUUAGUUUGAAUAAUAGACUUUCAAGUUCAAAAAUCAGAACAUAGCAAACCAUGCAGAAAAUUUUAGAACACAGAGGGAAACCUACCAAGUACACAUUAUCCUAACCACUCUGUGCUUCUUUCCAAGCUUUCCCCAGUAUGAUCAUACAUGGCCAUCCUGAUACAUAGACAUUUUGUUUUCUUGUUUCCACUUAAUAUUUUAUUAUAAGUACUUUUCCCAAGUUGUUACGUAGUCUUCAAAGCCAUUUUCCCCUCAGCUGUAUAGUAAUCCUGUUAAGGUUCUGUGGCAAAUGAUCAUGGUCUGAAAGGCAAGCUCAUCAUAGCACUCGUCUCCCACUGGGAGAAGGGGGUCCGGGCCGGGAGCUGAAUUAGACUUUGGAGUGCUGGGACCCUAGAGGAUGGACUCCCUACUGGUAGUUGGAACCCCCAUCCCAUGUGAGAUCUGGCCUCUGACUGAAUGUCCCAAGCAACUGGGUACUCCUUUUCCAUUCUUAGAUCAUUCUAUUAAGUCUAAAUGACAUGUGAGUAUCCAGGGUAUUUGGUGAGUGUUUCCGGUGGACGUUCCCAUGAAGUUAUUUACCUAGUCCUGACCUGCAGAUAGACGCAGAAACUGUCUAGGGGCAGCCUGGCCUAGUUGCUUUCUGAUCUGUACCAGGCACCCAAUCCUUACACUCUACCUCAUGUUUUCUGCUGAGGAAAGGGAUAGUAGUGAAUGGUACUUACUUCUUCGCAGAAAUGGUAUGAGAAUUAACAUAUCAAAAGAUCUAGCUGCCUUAUAUAUGAUGCUGAUGUCUUUUUAAGACUUUUCUAAAUUGUAGUUUUUUAGCUAUUUAUUAGCUAUUAUUAUUGGUUACUUAUUAGAUUUCAAUCAGGGAUCUGUAGAACAAGGGAAUUAAUGCCUCAAAUUCCCUUGUUCUCUCUCUCAAAUUCCUUAUUUCAUGGCACUUUUUUUCCCUGAAUAUUUUUUGGAGCCAGCUGCAUUAUAGGAUCUGUUUAUCUAUAUAUCCAUAUUUGUCUCUCCGACUAAACUGUAGCCUCUGGAGGGCCAAGAUCCUACCUCAUUUAUUUAUUUCUGAGUUCCCAGAAUCGAGCCAUUCAUCUAACAGGUAUUUACCAAGUGCCUUCUACAUGCCAGGCAUGGUUCCAGGCUCAGUUAGACAGCAGUGGACAAAACCCCCCAUCUUCAUGGAGCUUAUGUUGCAGUGGGGGCUACAGCAUAAGCAGUAGAUGAUGCAGCUUGUUAGAAGGUGGUUCAUGAUAUGGAGAAAUAUGCAGCAGUUGUGGGGGCUGGGAGGGUCUGAGGUGGGUUUGCAGUGUUAAAGCUGGAUCACCAGGAGGCAUCCCUGAGAAGGUGGUCUGUGAGCUAAGGCUGGAAAGAGAUGAGUCGGGAGGCCGCACCAGGCUGAGGUGCCUCUGAGGCCCAGACUGCAGAGUUGAGGAACAGCAGGGAGCCUGCUGAAACUGGCAUAGAAUUGGGGUGGGGACACACAGGAGGAGAGGAAAGUACAGGUGCCAAGUUGGGCUUAUAGAUGAAAGUUAGGACUGGCUUUUACUCCCAGUGACGUGGGCCACCUUGUAGAGGUUUGAGCAGAGGAUCGACCCAAUUAGUGGGCUCGAGUGGAGAACACACUGAAAGCUGGGGUGAGGAGGGCACAUGGAAGACCACGGAGGAGGCCACUGCAGUGGUCCAGGCCUGAGAUGGUGCCUUCAGCCAGAGUGGAUGUGGUGUGGUAAGAAGGAACAGAUCUUGCAUGUUUUCGCAUUCUGAUUUUAUUUUAAAAAUGUCCAUAUACCUGCAGAAAACAUGAGUGAUACAAUGAACACCUAUGUAUUCUUCACCUAGCUUUACCAGUUAUAAAUAAGUUGUCACAUUUGUUUUAUCUAUUAUUAUUAUUACUGUUGGCUAAAGAUUUUGGGAGGAAGCUACCUAUAGCAUAACCUUUCAGCCCUAAGUGCUGCGUGUUUCUCUUGGGCACAAGGACAUCCUUGUACAUAACCAUAGUAAAGUUAUCAAAUUCAAGAAGUUUAACAUUGGGAACAAAGAUUCACAUUUCUCCCAUUGUUCCAAUAAUGUCCUUUGUAGCCAUUUUUUUUUUUCUCCCCUGUGCAGGAUCUGAUCCAGGAUCACACAUUGUAUUCGUUUUUUUCUAUCUUUUAAUUUUAGAGUAUCUCUCAAUUUGGGUUUUCUGAUUCUUUUCGUACAAUUGGGUUCCAGUGGUAACUUUUUGGCAGGAAUGCUACACAUGGGAUAUUGUGUCUGUCUUAGGGUACUGGAGAUGCAAAUGUGAAGGUAGCAUCAGUGGGAUUUGUUGACAGUUUAAACUCAUAUCCCAGGCAUAUGAAGUGCUUUCAGAUCCAAAGAAAAGGGAUGUUUAUGACCAAGGCGGAGAGCAGGCAAUUAAAGAAGGAGGCUCAGGCAGCCCCAGCUUCUCUUCACCCAUGGACAUCUUUGACAUGUUCUUUGGUGGUGGUGGACGGAUGGCUAGAGAGAGAAGAGGCAAGAAUGUUGUACACCAGUUAUCUGUAACUCUUGAAGAUCUAUAUAAUGGAGUCACGAAGAAAUUGGCCCUCCAGAAAAAUGUAAUUUGUGAGAAAUGUGAAGGUGUUGGUGGGAAGAAGGGAUCGGUGGAGAAGUGCCCGCUGUGCAAGGGGCGGGGGAUGCAGAUCCACAUCCAGCAGAUCGGGCCGGGCAUGGUACAGCAGAUCCAGACCGUGUGCAUCGAGUGCAAGGGCCAGGGUGAGCGCAUCAACCCCAAGGACCGCUGCGAGAGCUGCAGCGGGGCCAAGGUGAUCCGUGAGAAGAAGAUUAUCGAGGUACAUGUUGAAAAAGGUAUGAAAGAUGGGCAAAAGAUACUAUUUCAUGGAGAAGGAGAUCAGGAGCCUGAGCUGGAGCCUGGUGAUGUCAUAAUUGUGCUUGAUCAGAAGGAUCAUAGUGUCUUUCAGAGACGAGGCCAUGACUUGAUCAUGAAAAUGAAAAUUCAGCUUUCUGAAGCUCUUUGUGGCUUCAAGAAGACGAUAAAAACAUUGGACAAUCGAAUUCUUGUUAUUACAUCCAAAGCAGGUGAGGUGAUAAAGCACGGGGACCUGAGAUGCGUGCGCGAUGAAGGAAUGCCCAUCUACAAAGCACCCCUGGAAAAAGGGAUUCUGAUCAUACAGUUUUUAGUAAUCUUUCCUGAAAAACACUGGCUUUCUCUGGAAAAGCUUCCUCAGCUGGAAGCUUUACUCCCUCCUCGACAGAAAGUGAGGAUUACAGAUGACAUGGAUCAGGUGGAGCUGAAGGAGUUUUGUCCCAAUGAGCAGAACUGGCGUCAGCACAGGGAGGCCUACGAGGAGGACGAAGACGGGCCCCAGGCUGGAGUGCAGUGCCAGACGGCAUGACGUGGUGCGGGGCAGCGUGGCCCCACCGGACUAGCACAUGAUGAAUGUAAAGUUGGCACAAUGAAAAUGACAUCGCUUUAAUGGCCUUGUGUUUGGGAUGUCCUGUGUAUGUGUUCAGCAUUCUUAAUUGCUGAGUGUCUUUUUGGCUUUUCUUUUGGUUGUAACUUAAGUUAUAGCUUAAUUUAUAUUUAAAUGUUUUAAGUAUAAAUCACCUCUAGUCUGCAUAUGGAAUCUGUUCAUUUCUAUUUUCAGGAUAUACUUUUGAGAUGUCAGUGAUUGCACCAAUACUUUGUGCUUCUAGUGGCUUUGCCAUAAUUCAGUGUCACCAAUAAGGCACAGCCCAGUUAGCAGCUUAGCCCCCCUAGCAAACCCCAAGGCACAAAGUGGGCAUCCUGACUCAUCUCUAGGUCUGUGGUUUCUCCCCUCUUCCCUUGGCAGAGUUAUUGAGGGCAUGAUCUCAGGGCUGCUAAGAUAACAUUUCUGAGGAUUCUAGAUGAUCCUCUUAAAGAAUAAAAGCACAUCCGUGGAUCGGACAUGGCUGCAUGUGCCUGCUUAACAGGGCCAACUUAGUUCCUACUGUUCUGUGCCCUUCAGUGGAUGGAACGUGAGUGUCUGAUCAUCUCUCUUGGAAGUUUUCUGAACCUUCCAAGCUCUGUGGUGAGGACAAACCAGUGUUUGAAUCAUAUGCUGAUAACUGUUUGCCUGUGACCCUCACACCUUGUUCUUCAGGGUUUUAAUGAUUUUCUGUUGACAACUUUUGCAAUGCUUUCCCACCAAAGUGCUUACUUGUAAAGAAAACUAAAUCCUUCUGUGUCCCCGGCAGCCUCAGUGCAGCAACAGAAGCCAAGGGAGAAUGCUGCUGGUUUGGCCCAUGGCACAGCCAGCUUCUCUGACCAGUAAUCCGGGGUGACUUGAGGGUCUGCAAAGGCAUAGAACUCCCCAGUGUUUUCCACCUCAUUCUCCCAGAUUGAGCUCCCUUCCAAAGGAUCGUUCCUCUCAUUGCACAGCCAUAUUACAAAGGGUUUCCUGCUCAAGUGAUGUUUUGGUAAGAACUUCGCUGAGUUCCACUGUGGAUUACAGUUUGUAUGGACUACUACUGUAAAUUAUAGCUUGUUUGGAGGGAUAUUAGUCAUUAUUUUAUUCAUGACAGGUAGACUACAAUUCGAACUUAGGGUUACCUCAGUCUUUAGCCAUUACUGCUUAUUUCUUUUCCCCAAGUCACAAAAAACUUGUAAGCUGCUGGGUUAAAGCAGAGGCCACCUGUCAGAUCUACCCUACCCUUAUUUGGUUACAUGGCACCUGAGAGUUUCACUCAGACCAGGGAUCUUCCUUAGGAGGGUCAAAGUGCAGAUCAGACCAUGCAGGUAAGGUGAACCAGCUGCACGGACCAGGUUCCCGCAAAACAUUGCCAGCUAGUGAGGCAUAAUUUGCUCAAAGUAUAGAAACAGCCCACCUGUGCCCACUUUGACCAUUGGUGAGGAUAGAUAUAAAAUCACUUCUUCCAACGAAGCCUAGGUGAAAAUCUAUUUAUAAAUGGACCACAACUCUGGGGUGUCGUUUUUGUGCUGUGACUUCCUAAUUAUUGCUAAAGAACUACUGUUUAGUUGGUAAUGGUGUAAAAUUACAUUCAGCUCCUUCUUGUCAUAUAAAAGGAAUUUGGAGGGUGUCGCUUAAAAUUUUAUUCCACCUGUACAUUUGUCACUUUAAAAUUAAAAUUGAGCUGGUAUGAGA